CCACCCGGCAGCACCCAAGAGCGGGGACCAGGCAGGCCCAGGGCUGGCCCUCGGCCAUGAUGGUGGGAGCCUGCGAGGCAGACGCACAGCUGGAGCCAGUGCUGAGCCGCCCCUGGGCCUGGGCAGAAGGGCACACCUCAGAUGUUGGACUGGUUCGUCCCACUGGGGCUUUCCUUUCAAUCAAGGGCUUCUUUUUCUUUUAAUUUUUCGGGUAAAUUCAGAACCACAGGUUUUCAAUUUUAUGUGCCGAGACUGUUGUUUUUUUCACGUGGAAAUCUUUUGGGAAUUUCCACAUGUACUACAGACGGGUAACUCAGGGGGCAGAGGUGUAGCCCCCUCCAUGGUGCCCCUGGGCCCAUGUCGGGGGCUGCAGCUGCCAUGGGGAGCACAGCCCUCCUGGUCUUCUUGACAGCUGCAGAUUCCCAUUGCACAGAUGGGGAAACCGAGGCUCUGAGGGCUUAUACUUGCACGUGGGCACACUGCUAGGAAGCAGCAGAGGCAGGCCCAGAAUUUCCAUCUGCCUGAUUGCAGAACCUGAGCUUGGGGGUCCUGGGGGGUUGACUAAUGCUGGGCAGUGAUAUCCGGGUGUUUGCGGCUGGUCCCUUGUCCAGCAGUGACUUGGAUUGAGGAAGAUGGAGCCUGUGCUUGGGUCCUGCUCAGUUCCCAAGAUGUGCCUCAGAGACUCUGUGGUUUCCAGAAUCCAUGGGCAACCCAGGGCCAUGCUGCUAGCUGCUCCACACAGCCCCAAGCUUGUUCAGUGGGCAGGUGGAGGCCUGCUUUUAGACAGAUGGGGGGCUUGGGCAAGGUAGAUGAAGGGCUUGAUUGAAAAGAGCUUUUGCUAAAUCAAUUGGCCGUACUUUCUUUCAUAUAUUACUAUUUUACAUGCAAUAUUAUGUUCAUGUAAUAUUGAUCAGAAAGCCAGCUGUAAGGUGCUUUUAUUUUAAUGGGAGUGAAGCAUGACAGGAGGCUUCCAUAGCGCCUUAGGGGACAGAUUUCCUGCUUGGCACUAGGUGGUUCCUGUCCAUGUUAAGCCCCUUGCUGCAGAGAUGUGCUUGUGGCUGGGGUUGAAGCCUGGCUGUGAGCUCCUCCUCCCUGUCGGAGGCUGUGGUGCUUCACACAGCUCUUUGGGGGAUGCCUGUCUUCUGGGAAGAAGUAUGCACUAGCUGACACCUCAGUGACUGGCCUCAGGGGCAGGAGAGGCCCCUAAACACCCUAGGCCCCUCCCGAGGUCCAUGGAGAGGCCUGGGGGUCCUGGGGGUUGGGGGUGUCUGAGGCCACCCAAGAUGAGGGCAGACAGGGCCAAAAGCCUGGGGGCCACCAGGUGCUUUAUUGUGGGCACCUGGGACUUGCAGGGGGAGUGGAGAUGGGGACAGAGGUGGGGAGGGUUUUGUGCUCAGGUCUGUGAGGAGGCGCUGUGUCCUGGGCUCCCCGCUGUGAAUCUGAGCCCAGGAGUAGGGCAGCCCAUCUGUGGACACACUGAUAACAAAAGACCCAGAGCUUCCCCGCCCCGCACAACUAGCCCGUGCCUCGGAGCAGUGUGCACGUGCACAUGUGCCUGCUAGGGGCCACUGAGGCCGCCGGCCCCCCUCAGCCCGCUGCAGGCAGUUCCUCUCCCAAAGUCUCCCAUUUGGAGCGUAGGUCAGUUUUUGAUGGUCUAUUUGCUCUGUUUUAAGUAUCGGCUGCUUGGAAAAAACUGCUGAAGAAAAUGGAGGAAAAUAUGUUAAUUUAUUGUGAAUAGUUUGCUCAGUGUUUAUUGCUGGGGGAAAAGGAAAGGAUUUGAGUAUGAUAAUUGGUGGAUUAAAAGUAUUAUUUUCCAUGCCGACUAGUUAGACGUUGCUCAUUGAUUCACCAGCAACCCUGCGGGACCUGGGCAUGCAGUCCUCACCCUCUUGGGUUGCCCAGACGGCAUGGCAUGGACCCUCGUAGUGGGUGUCCCUGGCCACCCCCCAGCCCCCCGUGGCUAAGUGCAGGCCCCCGCCCUCCAGUCUGUCUGGGCCUUGCAGGCCAGUUGAGGGGUCGGGGCAGGGCCUGCCAGAGGAUGCAGGGCAAGCUGCGUGCUCUGGCUGGCUCCUGAGCUGGGGCUGGGAGAGCCUGCUUCUGCGGAGAUGUCAGUGAGGGCAGGAGUGACUGCGCUCACUUAGGCAGGCCUUCAGUGCUGCAGCUUGUGUGGCAGGGGCAGUGUGGUCCUGGCACUGUGGGGGCAGCUCCCGGCAGUGCCUUCUGAGGAGUGCUUGAGGCUGACCAUGCUUGAUUUUCCCAUUGUUGUGGCUUUCACACCUCAAUCCUGCUCAGUCCCUGUGAAACCCAAAAUGCAACGCAGUCCAGUAUGUCUCAGACAGGGCCUGGGAGGUGGCAUUGGUGAGGGCUGCAGUGAGGGCGCCUGCCCCGGCACUGGGCAUCUUCCUGAGUCUGCCGGACCCUCAGAGAGCAGUGGGUUCGGGCCUCAGCACUGUCCAGCAUGGGUAACUUUUGUCCAAGUUGCCUCACCAGCCCUAGGACUCCCUCUGUGUCUGGGCUCCCUGUGGCAGCUUCCUCUCCCUGUCCUGCUGUAGCAGAGCCUCAGUCUUGGGAGCCCUCUUGCUUCUGAACCAGGACUGGUCCUGGUGGGGCCACUGCCCUGGGUGCCUCAGUCUCUGUGUCUGGUAACAGAGGUGGGCACAGGCAUGCAGAGCUGGGUGGCCCGCCUGCCACUGUAUUGGCCUCUUCCUUCUUGUCUCACAUGUGUGCUGUCUCUGGCAAGGGGUUCUGGGUAUACAAGCCCCCAUUACAGUGCCUGGAUGUGCUCACAGCCACAGGCUUCCCAGCCCCUCUCAUCUGAAUGGUUUUACUGAAAGUGCCUCCAGUGCUUCUGGGAAGUGGUGGAGAGGGGAUGGGCAGCUCGAGAGACAGUGAUGCUGAUGCAAGAGUCCUGAAGGGGCAGGUCCAGGGAGCAGAGGGAGAGGACGGCAGGCACCCCGUGUGCCCCAAGUAUGGGCCCAGGAGUGGCUAGAUGCAGUGACAGGUGUGGCUGGGCCUCCCCUGUAAGGUGGGGCGGGCUGCCUUGUCCUGGGGCCAGGUUUGAGCCACAGGGAAGUGGGCAGGGGUGAGGACUAGAAAGGGACGUUGCAGGGUGUACCUGCUGGGCUGGACCACGUGAGUGGUGGGGAAGCCUGGGGCACCUGUCCUGGCUACAUACAGCAUCUGGAGCCCAGGGCAGGCCCCUGACUCAGAGUUUCUGGGUGGGGCCUGGGCCUUGACAUUUAUAAAGCUUCCCAGGUAGUUCUGGUGCACAGACAGGUGAGGGUCCUGGCUGCAGGGGGUUGUGGGCGGUGGGGCAGGGCCCUGUGAAGAGGCCAGGGCUGCAUCCCAUGGGAGGGCCUGGCAGGGAGGUCCCCAAGGAGCCCAGGACUUGGCCUUGGGGGUCCUUGCUGUCCAGCAGCACCAAGCCCCUGGUUCUGUGGGAUGACAGUGGUCACCCCAUUUCACCACUCUGUGAGCCUAGACAGGCUGAUCACACACUGGGUGUCUCAGAAGAUUCUUCUGGAAGGAGGGGAGCCAGUGUAGACAGGAGGAGGUGUGUGCAUAGGCAUGGGGCAGAGGAGGAGGAUGCGGAUGCGAGACAGGCUGGGCGCUAUGGGAGGGGCCACCUGAAGCUGAGGGCAGCGGGGGUGCAGACAGGGCAAAGAGAAAGCCUGGGAGUCUGUGUGGAGCCUGCCAGAAGUGGGUGAACUUGGACUGAGCUGAGGUGCAGCUGUGUCUGUUCAGGUGCAGAUGCAGCUGCAGGUCUAUGUUCAGGUGGGUGCAGGUGUGGGGGUAGGUGCAGGUGUAGAUGCAGGUGGGGGUGCAGGGUGGGGGUAGGUGCAGGUGUAGACGCAGGUGGGGGUGCAUGUGUGGGGGUAGGUGUAGGUGCAGAUGCAGGUGUGGAUGUAGGUGUGGGAGUAGGUACAGGUGUAGAUGCAGCUGUGGGUGUGGGAGUAGGCACAGGUGUAGUUGCAGGUGUGUGGGAGUAGGCACAGGUGUAGAUGCAGGUGCGGGUGUGGGAGUAGGCACAGGUGCAGAUGCAGAUGUGGGUGUGGGAGUAGGGUCAGGUGUAGAUGCAGAUGUGGGUGUGGGAGUAGGGUCAGGUGUAGAUGCAGGUGUGGGUGUGGAUGUAGGUACAGGUGUAGAUGCAGAUGUGGGUGUGGAUGUAGGUACAGGUGUAGAUGCAGGUGUGGGUGUGGAUGUAGGUACAGGUGUAGAUGCAGAUGUGGGUGUGGGAGUAGGGUCAGGUGUAGAUGCAGAUGUGGGUGUGGGAGUAGGGUCAGGUGUAGAUGCAGGUGUGGGUGUGGAUGUAGGUACAGGUGUAGAUGCAGUUGUGGGUGUGGAUGUAGGUACAGGUGUAGAUGCAGGUGUGGGUGUGGAUGUAGGUACAGGUGUAGAUGCAGGUGUGGGUGUGGAUGUAGGUACAGGUGUAGAUGCAGAUGUGGGUGUGGAUGUAGGUACAGGUGUAGAUGCAGGUGUGGGUGUGGAUGUAGGUACAGGUGUAGAUGCAGAUGUGGGUGUGGGAGUAGGCACAGGUGUAGAUGCAGGUGUGGGUGUGGAUGUAGGUACAGGUGUAGAUGCAGAUGUGGGUGUGGGAGUAGGGUCAGGUGUAGAUGCAGAUGUGGGUGUGGGAGUAGGGUCAGGUGUAGAUGCAGAUGUGGGUGUGGGAGUAGGGUCAGGUGUAGAUGCAGAUGUGGGUGUGGGAGUAGGCACAGGUGUAGAUGCAGGUGUGGGUGUGGGAGUAGGUACAGGUGUAGAUGCAGGUGUGGGUGUGGAUGUAGGUACAGGUGUAGAUGCAGGUGUGGGUGCGGAUGUAGGUACAGGUGUAGAUGCAGGUGUGGGUGUGGAUGUAGGUACAGGUGUAGAUGCAGAUGUGGGUGUGGGAGUAGGCACAGGUGUAGAUGCAGGUGUGGGUGUGGAUGUAGGUACAGGUGUAGAUGCAGGUGUGGGUGUGGAUGUAGGUACAGGUGUAGAUGCAGGUGUGGGUGUGGAUGUAGGUACAGGUGUAGAUGCAGAUGUGGGUGUGGGAGUAGGGUCAGGUGUAGAUGCAGGUGUGAGUGUGGGAGUAGGCACAGGUGCAGGUGCAGGUGUGGGUGUGGGAGUAGGCACAGGUGCAGGUGCAGGUGUGGGUGUGGGAGUAGGCACAGGUGUGAGUGUGGGAGUAGGCACAGGUGUACAUGCAGGUAUGGGUGUAGGUACAGGUGCAGAUGCAGGUGUGGGGGUAGGUAUAGGUGUAGAUGCAGGUAUGGGUGUAGGUGUAGGCACCAGUGUAGAUGGAGGUGUGGGUAUGGGUGUAGGCACAGGUGUAGAUGCAGGUGCGGGGGUGGAGGUAGGUACAGGUGUAGAUGCAGGUGUGGUUGGAGGUACAGGUGUAGAUGCAGGUAUGGGUAUAGGAGUAGGUACAGGUGUAGAUGCAGGUAUGGGUAUAGGAGUAGGUACAGGUGUAGAUGCAGGUAUGGGUAUAGGAGUAGGUACAGGUGUAGAUGCAUGUAUGGGUGUAGGUGUAGGAACAGGUGUAGAUGCAGGUGCAGGGGUGGAGGUAGGUACAGGUGUAGAUGCAGGUGUGGUUGGAGGUACAGGUGUAGAUGCAGGUGCAGGUGUGAGGGUAGGUACAGGUGUAGAUGCACGUAUGGGUAUAGGAGUAGGUGCAGGUGUAGAUGCAUGUAUGGGUGUAGGUGCAGAUGCAGGUGUGGGUAAAGGUGGGGGUGUGGAGAGAAGUUGCAGGUCACUGGGGAAAGCGUGUGCCAUGGGAGGGAGUGGGCUACGCUGCCCCAUCUCAGGGUGACACAUGGGAAGGUUCCCUACAAAGUGGGGUAAGGAAUGCCCAGGGCUAGUUCUGUAGUUGGGAGAGAGGCACAGGGUGGACCGAGGGGGUACACAGAGUGGCUGGGGUGCAGGAGGAAGGUCACUGAGUCGGCUUGCUGGCUUUAAGGUGUGAGAGACCAGUGCGUGACCAUAUGAGGGUCUGGACCCUCCUUCCCAUCUGCUGUCUUCCGUCUCCUCUCCAUGCCCAUCUCUGUCUCCAGGCCUCCAGCCCUCCCUGUGGCAUAUGGGUGGAUGAGCAGAGCUGGAUGAGGGGAGUGGCUGGCCUCUUCCAAGGGAGAAGUCAUCAGCUCACUGCCACCCUCUCUGCUCCACGCCCUCUGCCUGCCACCUGGGCCAGGAGUUUGUGCAGGAGUUUGUGCAGGCCAUAGGCUGUUGUUUAAGUGCCUGGGCUGCAGGCCAAGAGCACUGGGCUGAGUGCCUGUCUCUCUGUGC